ACACGGAAAUGUAUUUUCCUGGCUGCAGCACCUGCCAUCUUGCCUCGGUAGGACUCAUUUUCAAAAACAGCAGCUUCUUGAAGCCCCAGAACGCAUUCCUGUGCUACGGAAGACGGAAGAGUAGCUCUCGGGGUCAGAAGGCGAAGGUCAGAAGGCCGAAUUGGCGGGAGAAUAGGUUUGGUGGUCCGAGAUCCGAGGCAACGGUGGCUCCUCGAGGUCCACGGUCCCGGGAGUAAUGUGAGGAUUCUUGCUUUUCUGGAAGCUAACACAUAGUCAGUGCCAAAGUAGUGACAGAAGAAAUCUUGAGAGGAAGCAUUUUUGUCUUGUACUUGAAACAGCUGCUGGGCCCACCAUGGCUCCUGUGAAGAUCAGCCAUGUGGUAUCAUUUUCUUCUCAGGAUCCCAAGUAUCCUGUAGAGAACUUGCUAAACCCAGAUAGUCCAAGGAGACCUUGGCUCGGCUGCCCUCAGGACAAGAGUGGGCAAUUGAAAGUAGAACUACAGCUGGAGAGGGCAGUGCCCACUGGCUACAUUGAUGUGGGUAACUGUGGCUGUGCGUUCCUGCAAAUUGAUGUGGGCCAUUCUUCCUGGCCCCUGGACAGACCUUUCAUAACCCUGCUCCCUGCAACCACGCUAAUGUCUCUAACUGAUUCAAAGCAGGGGAAGAACCGCUCCGGGGUCCGCAUGUUUAAAGAUGUUGAUUUCCUGGCUCCAGCCUCAGGAGAGUUAUGGGAUCGACUUCGCCUGACCUGCUCCCGACCCUUCACGCGUCAUCAGUCCUUUGGCCUGGCCUUUCUACGGGUGUGUUCUUCUCUGGACUCCUUAGAUGACUCUGUGGUGGGUCCCUCAGCCCUUCUGAGCUCUGUGCUGAACAAGAUAAGAGAGUUUAAGACAUGUUUUUUCUCCUGGAGUCUGAAGAAGAUGGAGUUAGAAUUUUCACCACUUCUUUUGUCCAUCAAUUUGAAUGAUCUUCAGUUUGCAGCAGAUGCUGAAGUCAGCACAGUAUCUAAUUGCAUGUUCAUCAGCAUUGCACUUCAGUCUGCAAUGAUAAUAUUCUGAAGGACAUUCAUCAUUAGAAGUGAAGCUUCUGGCUUUAAAAAGAGAAGACAAAUUAUAUGACACAAUAUUACUUACUUUUUAUGUUUAAAUGUCUGAAAUGUUUUAUAAUAAAUUAAAAGCAUUACAGAACUUUCCCAGAAAAACAAAAACAACAGCAAAAGAAUGCAAGAGAAAAAGUGGAGAUGCUGAAUAAAGACAAACGAUGAUUUCUUCUGUAAAGAGAGUAGUAAAUGAGGCAGUAGUUGGAAAUGUACAGAAUUUUAAAUGAGAACUAUUACCACAUAUUUCUACCUAAAAUGAAUUAUCCAGCUUGGGGGUGGUGUAGAGAUUCAUAAUGCAGGAAAUAAUGUUUAAUUUCUGGAGUUAAAUUCUUAAAAAAGUCAUUGGGGAUGGAAUCUAGUGUAAGUGGAGGGGUUGGCCUUGAAUCACAGAGUGAAGAGAAGGCAGAUUAUGGAUAAAGAUAAAACCAUGUGAAGAGAUAUGGUGGUGGAAAAGUGGAAAAGCUAUCUUUGGUUGCUUCUCUGUUCUUGGUGAAAUGAGAAAAAAGAAUCCUUAAUUGAGAGAAGGGGUCAGAAGGAGUUGAGUCUUAGUUCCAGCUUCCCAGUGUAUUCGGGCUCAAGGCCAUGUCUCCUUUACUGAGGAAGUUACUGAGAUAUGGACAGGAGCCUAUAACCCAUAAUCUCCCAUAAAUAUUCCCUUUAAACAUACCAAUCCUUCCCAAAUCCUUUUGUUACAAUUUAUAAGUUAAAAUAUUUGCCAUGACCAACAUCAUGAAAGUUUCUCCUUAUGUUUUCUUCUAUAAGUUUUACAGUCUCAGGUAAUUAUGUUUAAAUGUGUAGUUCAUUUUGAAUUGCUUUUUGUGUGUAGUGUAAGAUACAGGCCCAGUUUUAUUCUUUUGCAUAUGAAUAUUCAGUUUUCUUAGUACCACGUAUUGAAGAAACCAUCUUUUCCCCAUUAUAUAUUCUUCGCAUGUUUGUUGAAGGCCAGUUGACUUUAUAAGUGUCAGUUGAUUUCUUGGCCCUCUAUUCUCUUCCAGUGGCCUAUAUGUCUAUCUUUAUCCCAGUAGCACACAGUUUUGAUUACUCUAUCUUUAUAAUACAUUUUGAAAUUAGAAAAUGUGAUGCCCCUAGCUUUGUUUUUCUUGCUCAUUGUUUUGACUAUUCUGGGUCCUUUGUGGUUUUAUAUGAAUUUUAAAAUUGUUUUUUCUAUUUCUGUCAAGAGUGCCAUUAGGAUUUUGAUAGGGAUUGUAUAUAAUCUAUAAAUUGCUUUGAAUAGUAUGGAUAUUUUAAUAUUAUUAUGUCUUCCAAUUCAUGAACAUAGGAUAUCUUUCUACUGAUUUGUGUCUUCUUUAAUUUCUUUCAUGAAUGUCUGCAAUUUUUAAUGUACCAGUCUUUCAUCUUUUGGUUAAGUUUAUUCUUAAAUAUCUUAUCUUUUUCUUGCUAUUAUGAAUGGGAUUUUCUUUACUUGCUUUCCAGUUGCUUGCUGUUAGUGCUAUAGAAACACAACUGGUAUUUGUAGGUUGAUUUUCUAUCCUGCAACUUUACUGAAUUUGUUAUUAGUUUUAAUAAUUUUGGGGGAGUGAAGUUUAGGGUUUUUUACAAAAAAAUUAUGUCAUUUGGAAAUAGAUAAUUUUACUCAUUCCCACCCCCCAACAGUUUGGAUGCCAUUUAUUUCCUUUUCUUGCCUAAUUGUUCUUGCUAGAACUUUUAGAAUCAUGUUAAAUAAAUGUGGCAAGAAGGGGCACUUUUGCCUUGUUCCUGAUCUUAGAAGAAAAGCUUUUAGUUUUUCACCAUUGAGUAUGAGUGAAGAAUUUCUUUUUACUUUUAUUGUAAGGUAGGACUACUGGUGACAAACUCUAUUUUUGGUUACCUAAGAAAAUUAUGUAUUUUUACUUUAAUUUAGAGGGUAGGCUGGGCAUGGUGGCCUGCACCUUUAAUCCUGGCACUUUGGGAGGCCAAGGCGGGCAGAUCACCUGGGGUCAGGGGUUCAAGACCAGCCUGGCCAAACUAGUGAAACCCAGUCUCUACUAAAAAUACAAAAUUAGCCAGGCGUGGUGGUGGCUGGCUGAGGCACGAGAUUGCUUGGACCCAGGAAGCGGAGGCUGCAGUGAGCCAAGGUCACUGCCACUGCACUCCAGCCUGGGUGACAAAGUGAGACUCUGUCUAAAAAAAAAAGAUAAUUUUGCUAAGUAGAGAGUUUUAAGAUAGUGUUCUUUUUUUUUUUUUAACAUUUUAAAUAUUUCACUUUCCUCUCUUUUUGCUUAUGUGGUUUAAGAGAAGUCUGAUGUAAUUCUUAUCCUUGGUUGUCCAUAGAUAAAGAUUUUUUCCCCUCCUGGCUUCUUUUAAGAUUUUCUUUUCGUCUUUGAUUUUUGGCAGUUUCAAUAUAAUAUGCCUAUGUUUAAAUUUUUUGUAUUUAUCUUGCUUGGUAUUCUCUCAGCUUCCUAGAUAUGUAGAUUUUGUUUAUUUUCAAUUUUGGGAAAAUCUCAGUCAGAAUUUCUUCAAAUAUUUCUUCUGUUCCUUUCUUUCUCCUCCUCCUGAUACUUCAUUACACAUAUAUUUUUCCUUUUCUAAUUGGCCUACACUUAUUAAAUAUUCUGUUCUUUUUAAUUCUUUUUUCUUUGCUUUUAAGUUUUGGAAGUUGCUAUUUAAAAUUCUUUAAGCUCACUGAUUCUUUCCUUGAUCAUAUCAGUCUAUUGAUGAAUUCAUUGUUAUGGGCUAACCAGUUUUCCUCCAAAAUUUGUAUGUUAAAGUCCCAAUCUUUAGUAUCUCAGAAUGUAAUCAUAUUUGAAGAUUUUUUUUUUUUAAGGACUGAUAAAGCUAAAAUGAGACUCCCAGGGUAUGGCCCUCGUGCAAUAUGGCUGAUGUCCUUAUUAGAAGAGGAAGAGACACCAGGAAUUCAUGUGCACAAAAAAAUGCCAUAAGAGGACAUGGCAAGAAGGCAACCAGCUGCAAGCCAAGACAGGCCUCAGGAGAAACCAAAUGUGCUGACGUCUUGAUCUUAGACUUAUAACUUCCAGAACUGUGAGAAAAUGAACUUUUGUUAUUUAAGGCACCCAUUAUGUGGUACUUUAUUAUGAUAACCCUAUAGCAAUGCAAGAAUGGCCUAAUACAUCUAUAUUUAUAUUGGACAAAAUUGACUUUAAGUGAAAAAACAUAAAAAGAGACAAAGAAGGCCAUCAUAUAAUGAUAAAAGGGCCAAUCCAGCAAGAGGAUAUAAAAAUUCCAAAUAUGUAUAUAUAUGUACCCAGUAGUGGAAUAGAUAUAUUAAAAAUGUCAUUAGAGCUAAAGAGAGAGAUACACCUCAACAUCAUGAUAACUGAGGGCUUCAAUACCCCACUUUCAGCAUUGAACAGAUCAUCUAGGUAGAAAGCUAACAAAUAAUCAUCAAAUUUAAUCUGUACCACAGAACAAAUAGACUUAACAGACAUUUACACAACAUUUCAUCCAAAAGCUGUGGAGUACACAUUCUUCUCCUCAUCACACAGAACAUUCUCCAGGCUAGACCAUAUGUUAAGACACAAAACAAGUUUCAACAAAUUUUGAAAAAUCAACAUUAUAUCAAGUAUAUUCUAGACAAAAAUAGAAUAGAACUAGAAAUGAAUACUAGGAAGAACUUUGGAAACUAUACAGAUAACAUGGAAAUUAAACAACAUGCUUCUGAACAACCAUUGAGUCAAUGAAAAAACUCAGAAGAAAAUAACAAAUGUUCUUGAAAUAAAUGCAAAUGGAAACACAA